CUUUUUUUUUUUUUUUUUUUUUUUCUGUAGAGACAGGGUCUCACUAUGUUGCCCAGGCUGGGUUCGAACUCCUGGACUUGAGCAGCGCUCCUGCCUUGGCCUCGUGCAGUGCUGGGAUUACAGGUGUGAGCCAUGGUGCCCAGCUGAUAGAGCAUUUUUUUUUUUAAGACAGUCUCACUCUGUCACCUAGGCUGGAGUGCAGUGGCACAAUCUCGGCUCACUGUAGCCUCUGCCUCCCUGCAGCCUCCACCUCCCGGCUUCAAGCAGUUCUCACGCCUCAGCCCUCCAAGUAACUGAGAUUACAGGUGUGUGCCACCACGCCUGCUAAUUUUUGUAGUUUUAGUAGAGACAGGGUUUCACUAUGUUGGCCAAGCUGGUCUUGAACUCCCAGCCUCAAGUGAUCCACCCACGUUGGCCUCCCAAAGCUCUGGGAUUACAGAUGUGAGCCACUGCGCCCUGCUGGAGUAUUUUCGAUCCAAGAGAACAUCGUGGACAUUAUGUAGCAGCUUCCAGCCUUCUUUCUCAUAGAAACAAAGGCAGAGAAGCAGCACCCAGACUUUGGCGUGAAUGCUGAUGGGAUUUGCCGGGGGAUGUUACUGUGGUGAGGACCAGGCCCCUGCAGGUGUGCCCAACUCUGGAUGGCUCCCUGCCUUCACUGAGUCCAUCGUGUGCUUCUCUGCCUGGUCUGUUUUUCCGAGUCUUCGUCUUUGCCUGUCGACACCCCGUGACUGCUGGCAUCAUGCCUUCUUGUGGAAGCCACCAUCGUCCUUGCUAACUGAGGGUUGUGGAGUUGUGUAAUUCAGCUUGAUGCAGGGAGGAGGUGUAUUCCCAUGUGUGGGCACUGUCAUCACCCACACAGGGAGGUGAGCCCACCUCACAGAAGGAACACAGCCUGGCCAGGGGGCAGUCUGAGCCUGCGUGGGCUCUGCUGCAUUCUGUGUGGCUCGGCUCUCGGCACGCCUUGACUCAAGACUGCAUGGAUUCAGGGGCCCCUUCCUGGCUCAGAGGUGACCCCAGAGCUGAGGAGAACCUAGAGACAUGGUGGCUGGGGCUGGGCCAGCGCCUGGAGAGAGUCUGAAGCUGCCCUCACAGGGAUUGGGGAGGUGACCGAGGUGGGGUGCCUGUCCCCCUUCCCACCCCUCCCAGGCCUCAUUGGUGUCCACCAGGCACCUUCCACGUGUCUAUUUCCCGUAUUCUUGAGAACCUCUCCGUGAGGUUAGUGUUGGGUUUGCAUGUCUGUAAUUGAGGGAAGAUUUUGAGCCUGGGAGAGUUUUUGGGGGAGGUCCCCAGACCAUUACUGGUGCAGAGUGGAGCCCCUGCUGCUCUGGCUUCUGAUCCUGGUGUGUGCUCGCUCUAAGCUGCCCUGGGCUGACAGUGCCCUGCACCAGCCGCACUGCCCUCUCUGGGCUGCAAGCCGAGGAUCCCCAUCUGAGAAACAAGCAGCGGGUCCAGAGAGUUCCCCGCCUGGCUUCCAGCCCUGAUUGGUGGCUUCUCCGAGGCUGCAAGGCGGUGGUAAUCACGAGAGCCACGUCGUUGGUGGGUGUUCCCAUGUUGCAGGUACCGUCCUGGUACUUAGUAUCUGUUAACACACAAAUUCACGAGGAAUGCUCCCAAAGCACAGAGAGGUUAAAUUACUCAGUCUAAGGUCACGCAGCAGUAAGUAAUGGAGCUGGAAUUUGAGCUCUAACAGUCUGCUCCGGAGCUCGGGCCUUGCUGCUGGCGUCAGGCCAUGCACAGAGAGCUGAUGGAAGCAGGAGGAGCUGAUGUGAAGUUAUGCGACACACAUGGCCUUUUAGGUGAGCUCGGGCCACCCGGGGGGAUUUGUGUCCAAUCAGCAGGGGAGUUUCUAGUGUGCCAGGCAAGACACGCAGGAGAUCGUGAGGCUGAAUGGGCCUCGCGCAGGUCAGCUGUUUGAAUUUUGGACUGUAAAUGGUGGUGUGGCACCACGCUGCGGUCAGAUGAUGGUCUCUGUGUUGCACACAAACCAUAGGUUCUGGGCCAGGCAUGGUCUAUGCUGCAGAAGCUUAGGCUGCAGUGGCCUCCUCAAGGCCUUUCUGUGGGUGGAUAUGGCACAGGCGGCAACUGGGGCCGAUGCAGCGUGGACCGAGAUGGGUCUGGGUUAGUGCCAGCCUCCCACUGCUGCCUGUGAGGCCUCGAGCCUGCUCUCUGGCCCUCGGUGGCCUACAUUCCAGUUGGGAGAAAGCAAAUGUGGUGCACACAGUGUGCACCUGGUCUCUAAGACGGCCAGAUGUCAGCAGGGCACCCGCUAGGAGGCAGCACUGUGGAUGAGAGGCAAGAGCGGUGGAGUGGUCAGGGAGGUCUGAGUGAAGCAAGGGCAUGAGCUAGGGAUGUCCAGGCGGGGGGGCAGGUGUGAGGCUCUGGGCUUGGAGCCUGCUGGUGCCGGACAGAGUGGGCAGGUGGGUAGAGGAGGAGGAGAUGGGCCUUGGCCCUUAUUCUUUGGAUUUUGUUGUUUUGCUCUGGUGCCUGCGGGCAGCUAGUGUAGAGGUCUGAGGUCAGCGAGCACCCUUACUGAUUUGCAGGACUUGUUCAAGAGCCACGGAUCUUUCCAGAAAGUCACUUGUUGGAGGAGAGGACCUCCAAAGUCAACAAAGUCUCUGCUCUGCACUCCAUUCCCCCACGAAGUGCCAAAGCAAUGCACCCUACCUCCCCAAGUCUCUGGGAGUGGGCCUGGGAGACCCACCCAGGGAUCCAGCCUUUGCUGAUUGUGUUUGUGUCUGACUUGCCUGCCUUUCUGUGGGGAUCGCCCGCCCAUGCUCCUGUCCGACGUGGUGUGGGGCUGAGGGGGCUGCACACUGUCCUGGCCUCCCUUCCGAAGGGCUCCCCAGCGGGCAGUGCAAAACGUCAGGAAGUAGGUGGGAUUGUGUGUGGUUGUGACAUGGCAUGGCACGGGGCAUGUGGGUUUUGCUGCUGUUGGUGUUCGGUGCUGAGCUGUCAAAGGCUAGUGCUGGCUCUUACUACUGUUUUCCACUCUUCCCUUUUCAAGGAAUGUUCCAUUUGGCUGCUGCACUCCCAUCCACCCUGUGUACACAUCCUCCAGAGGCGAUCACCUCGGCUGUUGGGCUCUGAGGCCCGAGUGCCUUCGCAUAGUGUCGAGAGCGCCAUGGACCUCUACCUCUGUGGGUUUUGUGGCUGUGGGACCUCAGUGCCUUCCUGUGCGUGGCUGGCACUCUUCGCGCCCUGUUCGCGAUGACUCGGUAGUAGAGAAGUCCCUCAAGUCCUUGAAGGACAAGAACAAGAAGCUGGAGGAAGGCGGCCCGGUGUACAGCCCCCCCGCAGAGGUGGUGGUGAAGAAGUCCCUGGGGCAGCGGGUGCUGGACGAGCUGAAGCACUACUACCAUGGCUUCCGCCUGCUAUGGAUCGACACCAAGAUCGCGGCACGCAUGCUCUGGCGCAUCCUCAACGGCCACAGCCUGACCCGCCGGGAGCGCAGGCAGUUUCUCCGGAUCUGCGCUGACCUCUUCCGCCUGGUGCCGUUCCUUGUGUUCGUGGUGGUGCCGUUCAUGGAGUUUCUGCUGCCUGUUGCUGUGAAGCUCUUCCCCAACAUGUUGCCAUCCACAUUUGAGACUCAGUCACUCAAGGAGGAGAGGCUGAAGAAGGAGCUUCGGGUCAAGCUGGAGCUGGCCAAGUUCCUCCAGGACACCAUCGAGGAGAUGGCCUUGAAGAACAAGGCAGCCAAGGGCAGCGCCACCAAAGACUUCUCUGUGUUUUUCCAGAAGAUCCGGGAAACAGGGGAGAGGCCCAGCAAUGAGGAAAUCAUGCGUUUUUCCAAAUUAUUUGAGGAUGAGCUGACCCUGGACAACCUGACACGGCCGCAGCUGGUGGCCCUGUGCAAGCUGCUGGAGCUACAGUCCAUCGGCACCAACAACUUCCUGCGCUUCCAGCUUACCAUGCGGCUGCGCUCCAUAAAGGCAGACGACAAGCUGAUUGCUGAGGAAGGGGUGGACAGCCUGAAUGUCAAGGAGCUGCAGGCAGCGUGUCGGGCACGAGGCAUGCGGGCCCUGGGCGUCACGGAAGACCGCCUGAGGGGUCAGCUGAAGCAGUGGCUGGACCUGCACCUGCAUCAGGAGAUCCCCACAUCGCUGCUCAUCCUGUCCCGGGCCAUGUACCUCCCGGACACCCUCUCUCCAGCCGACCAGCUCAAGUCCACACUGCAGACCCUCCCAGAGAUUGUGGCAAAGGAAGCACAGGUGAAAGUGGCCGAGGUGGAGGGCGAGCAGGUGGACAACAAGGCCAAGCUGGAGGCCACGCUGCAGGAGGAGGCGGCCAUCCAGCAGGAGCACCGUGAGAAGGAGCUGCAGAAGCGCUCGGAGGUGGCGGAUUUUGAGCCCGAACGUGUGGUAGCUGCUCCCCAAAGGCCGGGGACCGAGCCACAGCCAGAAAUGCCUGACACAGUCCUGCAGUCAGAGACCUUGAAGGACACUGCCCCGGUGCUGGAGGGCUUGAAGGAGGAAGAGAUCACGAAGGAGGAAAUCGACAUCCUCAGCGAUGCCUGCUCUAAGCUGCAGGAGCAGAAGAAGUCACUCACCAAGGAGAAGGAGGAGCUGGAGCUGCUGAAGGAGGAUGUGCAGGACUACAGCGAGGACUUGCAGGAGAUCAAGAAGGAACUUUCAAAGACUGGUGAAGAAAAGUACGUGGAAGAAUCUAAAGCCAGCAAGAGAUUGACAAAAAGGGUGCAGCAAAUGAUCGGGCAGAUCGAUGGCUUGAUCUCGCAGCUGGAGAUGGACCAGCAGGCUGGCAAGCUGGCCCCGGCCAACGGCAUGCCCACGGGGGAGAACGUCAUCAGUGUCGCUGAGCUCAUCAACGCCAUGAAGCAAGUCAAGCACAUUCCCGAAAGCAAGCUCACCAGCCUGGCCGCAGCACUGGAUGAAAACAAGGAUGGCAAGGUCAACAUCGACGACCUCGUCAAGGUGAUUGAGCUGGUGGACAAAGAAGAUGUUCACAUCUCCACCAGCCAGGUGGCUGAGAUUGUAGCAACACUGGAAAAAGAGGAGAAGGUGGAGGAGAAGGAGAAGGCCAAAGAGAAGGCAGAGAAGGAGGUCGCAGAGGUGAAGAGCUAGAACCACUGGCCUGGGCACCUGUCCUCCUGCUGUGCCGUCACCCUGGCAAGGGCCGUGAGGGCGAUUGCUUUGUGGUGAUUCUCAGUGGCUCAUCUAAUAUUUUGGCUGGAAUAAAUCAGAGACUUCCAUAAUCAAGUAAAUUUUAAUUUUCAUCAUUCCACGGAGAUUCAGUCUGUCUGGAAUCCCGGAACCCCUCCACAGAAUCGUGUCUGGAUCCACACUGUGGUGUGGCUGCCACGGCCUCCUGGCUCCAGAGGCAGCUGGGCUGGGCCAAGGCAGGAAGGCGCCCCCAUGUGUGUGGCCUCAGUCUCAGCAUCUGACUGUGCUGCCCUGUCCCCAGGGAAGAGAAUGAGGACCACGUGGACUCCGCCCACACAGAGCUGGCUGCUGUGCCCACCCUCAGGGGCGUCAGGAGACACAGCCUGGCCUCCUCAGGGCUGAAGAUGCCUCCAUUCGCCUGUGGACCUUGAUUUCUAGAUUUCAGUGUCAAUAGACCUGUCUUCCUGCACACUUUCAGUUGGAUGUGGGUCAUUGUGGAGACAGAGGUGUCUGCCAUCUCUGUGGCCUCUGGAGAGUGACGUCUCCCUGCUGGGAGUGCUGGUUCUCACGUGCGGUUUCCCUUGUGUAUCGGAGCUCUUUCUCGGCUUUCUAUUUCCCCCAGUUCUUUAAGCAGUCAAUUGGCACAGAGUUUCCCACGGGGGCUGCAGUGGAUUCACUGUGUCAGGGAUGAGCCUGGCUUGGGGGUUGGUGGGGCUCUGAAGCGCAUUUGGGGUUCUUUGUAGCUUCUAAUGUGAGGUUUGAGUCCAGUGCGCCCACAGCAGCAUGCCCUUCUCACCCCUUGCAGUGUUGCAGGCUCAGGCCCCUGGGCUCCUUCAGCAAGCAGGCUAGUCAAUGAGGCAUGAGGAUCCGGCACAGGGCAUCCCCUGGGGCUUCAAGGGCAAUACCCCCGUGCUUAGGGUUUGCCCUGUGCCCUCUGGGUGGGGUGGCCUCCCCGCACUCGGCAGCAUGGCCAGGCUGGCCAGGGCGUGGGCAGGUGGUGUCCUGUGGCACCUCCAUCCUCCUGCCCAGCCGGCUGUGUCACACUCAUCUUUUUAAGGUCAGGUUGGUUCCUGGCAAAAAUGUACCUCCAGGGGCCUCCAAGCAUAGGAUUUGGAAGACAGGAACGGCACAGGCGUCCAGGAAAGCAGCUGCACUCAGACAAUGCCUUCUCCAUUACUUGAAGCUUCUUUCUGUUCAGCCAUUAAAGAAACUUGACAAAAUAGGAACAGGAGAUAUUUCUCAAUUGUAAACCUUUGUGCAGGGACAGUUGGCUUCCAGAGGCUUUCAGCUUUCAGUUAUUUGAGAAGUUUGUUUUAGAUCCUUAACUAAUAUUUAUGAAUUCUCUCACCCUGUGUAAGUAGCCUGGUGUUCGUUUGUCCAAGUGUACUUACCCUUGAGAACAAGUCUUGCAGUUGCCAGGUGUGUGCAGACGCCUCUCCUGUGAGCGGCAUCGCGGGCCCAGUCAGCUGCCCCGGCUCUCAUCCUCGUCCUCACUGCCUUGGCUGAGCACUGUUGACGUGAACAGCCACUGCAACAGGCAGCCCAUCCCACUGUCCCCUCUGCCCUGGACUCCGCAUGGCCUCCAAAAGCCAGCUUGCCCUCCGGGUGCUGCAGGGGCUUUGCAGGUGGGGAAGGCUCUGGUGGGUGCCUUUGGUGGCUUCCGUGACAUCAGCCGUGCUCUGAUGCAGGCUUGCUCCCUCGUCAUUCUCCCUCGUCAUUCUCCCUCAUCGUUCUGUGUGCAUUUUUCUCUAUGUCCUGACCUUUCUUCUUGCACCUAAAAGUGGUGUCUGGGUGCAAAUGUAAGCAGUGGUGGAUCCAGAAAUAUGAGCUUUGUGUAAUAAGCUUCUUAAAACAGUCCUUUCUUACACCUGCCCAGGGCCAGACCCUCGGUCUUGGCCUUUUUCAGGAGCUAGGAUAUCUGCGCCUGGUGAAAAUGAAACGAAUUCCUGAUUUAGGAAUUCAGUGUUUCCUCCUCACUCCAGCUAAGCACUCACUUUUUUUUUUUUUUUUUUUUUUUUUUGAUACAGAGUCUCGCUCUGUCACCCAGGCUGGAGUGCAGUGGUGCGAUCUCGGCUCACUGCAAGCUCCACCUCCCGGGUUCAAGCGAUUCUUCUGCCUCAGCCUCCUGAGUAAUUGGGAUUACAGGCAUGCGCCACCAUGCCCAGCUAAUUUUUUUUUUUUUUUUUGAGACAGAGUCUUGCUCUGUCUCCCAGGCUGGAGUGCAAUGGCGUGAUCUCGGCUCACUGCCAGCUCCGCUUCCUGGGUUCACGCCAUUCUCCUGCCUCAGCCUCCCGAGUAGCCAGGACUACAAGCACCCGCCACCACACCUGGCUAAUUUUUUUGUAUUUUUAUUAGAGACAGUGUUUUACCGUGUUAGCCAGGAUGGUCUCGAUCUCCUGACUUCGUGAUCUACUCACCUCGGCCUCCCAAAGUGCUGGGAUUACGGGCAAGUUUUUAUUAGAGAUGGGGUUUCAUCAUGUUGGUCAGGCUGGUCUUCAACUCCUGACCUCAGGUGAUCCACCCGCCUCAGCCUCCCAAAGUGCUGGGAUUACAGGCAUGAGCCACCGCGCCCGGCCUGAACUCUCAGUUCUAACGCAGGGAUUCAGGAAUUGGGCUUUCAGACUCCUUCUGCAGUGUCACAGUCCAGACUUUUUUUAAAUGAAGGACACCCCGCAGUGGCUCACAGUGGGUCCCAGGGCUAGCAGGAGCGUGCUGGGGAGCCGGCUCUGUCUUUGUUCGCAGUGGGUCCCGGUGCUGGCAGGAGUGUGCUGGUGAGCCGGCUCUGUCUUUGUAAAUCCUUCAGGGGUCCUACGGCUGACUCCACCGGACAGCCCGUCCUGGGCCGUGUUAAGCACCUUUUGUAGAAAUCGUAUUUUUAUUAAAACAUCAAAUCUGUGUUCCUGUAA